GGAUGAAGAGUAACGCCAUUACCGCCGGAGCCGCCGAGAGCCUUAGCCGACGGAAACUGGACACUGGACCGGCAGCGCCAUGAGACUCCUCCCCCGCUUGCUGCUGCUUCUCUUACUCGUGUUCCCUGCCACUGUCUUGUUCCGAGGCGGCCCCAGAGGCUUGUUAGCAGUGGCACAAGAUCUUACAGAGGAUGAAGAAACAGUAGAAGAUUCCAUAAUUGAGGAUGAAGAUGAUGAAGCCGAGGUAGAAGAAGAUGAACCCACAGAUUUGGUAGAAGAUAAAGAGGAAGAAGAUGUGUCUGGUGAACCUGAAGCUUCACCGAGUGCAGAUACAACUAUACUGUUUGUAAAAGGAGAAGAUUUUCCAGCAAAUAACAUUGUGAAGUUCCUGGUAGGCUUUACCAACAAGGGUACAGAAGAUUUUAUUGUUGAAUCCUUAGAUGCCUCAUUCCGUUAUCCUCAGGACUACCAGUUUUAUAUCCAGAAUUUCACAGCUCUUCCUCUGAACACUGUAGUGCCACCCCAGAGACAGGCAACUUUUGAGUACUCUUUCAUUCCUGCAGAGCCCAUGGGCGGACGACCAUUUGGUUUGGUCAUCAAUCUGAACUACAAAGAUUUGAACGGCAAUGUAUUCCAAGAUGCAGUCUUCAAUCAAACAGUUACAGUUAUUGAAAGAGAGGAUGGGUUAGAUGGAGAAACAAUCUUUAUGUAUAUGUUCCUUGCUGGUCUUGGGCUUCUGGUUAUUGUUGGCCUUCAUCAACUCCUAGAAUCUAGAAAGCGUAAGAGACCCAUACAGAAAGUAGAAAUGGGUACAUCAAGUCAGAAUGAUGUUGACAUGAGUUGGAUUCCUCAGGAAACAUUGAAUCAAAUCAAUAAAGCUUCACCAAGAAGGUUGCCCAGGAAACGGGCACAGAAGAGAUCAGUGGGAUCUGAUGAGUAAAUGUUCCUUUGUGCAACAAUUCGGUCUUUACUUAACCUGCCCUAAUAUUUUUCGGCCUGAUGGGAAUUAGUGCAGAGAAGCCAUGUCACCAUAGAAGGCAACUCCUACUUGUGUGUGGACUGAGCAAUCAGAGUCUGUGGCGAUAAUAUUGCUGAAAAUGCACUGCAUUCAUUUUUCUAAAGUAACAAAUUUGGUUUUUUUUUAAACCAUUAAAAUCUAUGUGUGUGCGUGUGUAUGUAUGUGAGCAGUUGGUCUUACCAGAAUCAUUGUUGAACUACCUGAAACAAGUCUUUAGAAUACUAAAUAUAAUGCUGUUGUCUCUUCCUUUUUGACAUUUUCUGAUUUUUUCCCCCAAAACUCAGUUAAUAUUUACCCACUAUGAUUAUUGAUGUCCUGCCUUGAACAGUUUUAAAGAAAACAAUUUUUGGAAUAGCUCAAAUUUCAAUUGAUGGCACAAAUCAGCAUUUUGUUGUUGUUACUGUAUUACAAUUAGUAUUCUAAAGGCAGAAGCAGAAGUAGCUGCUUUUUAGCAAUAGAAUUGUUUCAGUAUUUUGCUGCUGUUUAAUGCGCAUCUUCAGAAAACUUCCCAGUGGCUUCAAGGAAUUUGGGGAUCUCUCUGGCAACAAAUUGUGAAACAUGAAAUUUCUGCUGACUUUAAUAUAUGAAACCUAAUCCUACCCCCUUUUUUAACAAAAAGAAACUAGUACAUUUGUGAAAAUUGUGUUGUGUUGUCCAUUGUUGCUCUAGUUCUGACCCAGAGGUAGCUCUGGAGUGAUUUUAGACCUACUCACUCAGUUGUGUGUAGGUUUUUUUGUUUUGUUUUGAGAGAGAAUUUUUCUCUCCUUAAUAGAAGCAUCCUUUUUAAAGAGAAGUUGCCUUGGUCCACACACUAAGCAGAAAACCAAGUUAUCAGGACAGAGAUAUUUCCCAGUUACUCCUAAUCAAUGAAGAAAGUGAGUUGGAUAUUUUUAAAGCAGUUAACUAAUUUUUUCUUACCUAAUCUUUUGGGAGUUUUGCUUGUUGAUAUAACCUUUUUAGUUAACCUGAAAGAUUCCAAAAAUUGUUCUUAAGUGCUUGAGACUGGAACCAAAAUUAAAUUGUACUUCAUAAAAUCCUCUUAUAGAGUUACUCUUGCCCUAGAUUGUAAAUUAAGUUUGGCAUUAUUGUCAGACUGGAUGGAGGGUGAAGUAAAAUAGUAUGAACAAUUAAGAGGCUCUCCCCCUCUUGUCUUUAAGCCAUAUUCUCCUACAUGUAUUUUAUAAGAAAAUGUUAAGUCAAAUUUUAGUGGCUCUUUAAUUCCUGACCUCUUCAUUCUCCUUUUCAGUAUAACCUCCCCUAUGCUCAUGCCCACACAGACAAAAAAACAAAACGAAAUACACACAGAAAAAAGUCUUUCCAAACUGUUUAAGUAUUUAAACAUCUGAGCCAAAGCAGAUAGAAGUUAUUGUAUAAUUGUUAAUCACUUUGCAAAUAGGGGCUAUCAAAUUACCUAUAUUGGCAUUGCUGGAUUAUAAACUCUAUAUCUGUAAUAUAAAGUGUUUGAGUUUUUAAUUGGGCUGUUAUGAUCAGUAGUUGAUUUUGAGAAAGCUCUAUGAGCUCUAAGUAACUGCAUGGUUUUUUGUUUAAUGUAAUAUAGGAGACCCUUCACAUUCCCAAGGAAUAUAUUCCAAAACAUUUUUGUGAAUAUCUAAGUUUGUGAAACUACUAGGGCAUGAUACAGUAAGGUGUAAUUACAGAAUUUACGAAAUGUAAAUGGCCUCUACAGAGUUUUAUGGAAUACCUGGUACUAACGUAGGCAGCUGCAAAACCACACUGAGUUACAGCUGUCAGCCCUCCUCAUUCCUAAAUAACUUGCCUUACAUAUCAGCCCUCCCACUUCUGAAGUUCAAAUUAGUGCCUCGGAAAUGUAGAAUUUAUUAUUUGUCAUUUUUUUUUUUUUAGCAUAGAUUGAGAACAGUUGAACUCUUAAAUCCUCAGAUGCCAGGGGUCUGCUCUAGCAUCAGUAAGUAUUUAGCAGAAACUAACUCCGUAAUGAAUGGAAUUCAAUUCCACACAUGGUUUGUUCAAGCACACUUAAUAAGUAGCCUAUUUUUUAAAUGUCUUUUUAAAAUGUAAAUAUUUGGAUGAAGUUUUUCUUUGUUUUGAUAUAUUCAUUUGCUACACCAACUAUGUUUUCAGAAUUCAUCUUUUGAACAACUUGGUUUCAGAAUAUGUAAAAUGACUUUAAGGAUCUUGUGUAUCAAACCUAUCCCCGGAUGUGUGAGAAUAAUGUGUUCAUAAAGCAUGGAUCUCGCUUUGGUUGUAUAGCUUCCUCAUUUACUUCAUGGUCUUACAUAGCUGGUGACUUUCAGGGCUAAUCUGCCCUCUAAAGCAUUGUCCCAGGAGAGGAAAAGGAAAUGGGACCUCAGAAGUAGAAGCCUCAGGGAAGGAGUAAAGUAGAAAUCAGAAGAAAAGAAGCUUCACUUGAUAGUAAUAAGGUUUUUAACUUCAAGUACCUUCAGAAAAUGUGAUUUUGAUAAGAGGAAAGGGCAAAUUUAGACCUUAAAAAAUAUGGAAGAACUACUGCCUUAAAAGUGCAUUUGUGGCACAUCAGCCUAGAACUGUAUCAUGGCUGUGCUGGGGAGAAGUAAAUGGUGGUAAUGUAACAUUGCCACCUUUACUUAAUGAUGUGUUAUUUUCGAGGUACAGUAGAUCAAUAUAGUAAUAGGCGAGCCUCAUAUAUAGCAUUCAUCUUGUACAAUGAUAUCCAUACCCUUGAUAUGAAGGAAAAUUGACUUGGUUUGUGCAUUUGAAUACUGAAAUAAUUUUUUAAAACUCAGUGACACAUACCAUCUCUUGCCAAGACUAGACCCUGUAUUUUAGUUCCUAAAUUAGAUGUUUAAAUUUAAAAACAUUUUCAGAUGUACUUAAGUACUUCCAUAGUACUUUUUUUUUUUUUUUUUUUUUUGCCCCCUGAGACGGAGUCUCUGUGUCACCCAGGCUGGAGUGCAGUGGUGCGAUCUCGGCUCACUGCAACUUCUGCCUCUUGGGUUCAAGCAGUUCUCCCUGUCUCAGCCUCCUGAGUAGCUUGGAUUACAGGCGCCCGUCACCGCACCUGCCUAAUUUUUGCAUUUUUAGUAGAGACGGGGUUUCGUCAUUUGGCCAGGCUGGUCUUGAACUCCUGACCACAGGUGAUACGCCUGCCUUGGCCUCCCAAAGUGUGCUGGGAUUACAGGCGUGAGCCACUGUGCCCGGCCCACUGUUCACUUUUUGAAUGGCAUCAUUUUAUAGCUGUAGAACUAAAAUCAAUGUUUGCCCCAAUUUUCUUAAGUAAAACUCUACUUUGAGCUCUUACCUCCAACUUAGUAAAAAGCAGCUUCACACACAAACAAGAUUCUUACUGGUGGAAUGUUAGGUUUCGUUGUUAAGUUAAUCUGUCUAUAAGCUCAUCCUUAGAGGAUAUUUGAGGAGGAAGAACACCUUGCAGCUGACUUGCAAACAUCUAAAUAAUUUAUUUCGGGUGCUUAUGAAUGUUACUAAUGGAUUUUGUAUGAAUUUUUAUCCCUUUUCAUUUAUACAAAAACCUGGGCUUUUAUGUUAAUUAUAUCAUCUGAGGUUCUAAGGUUUUUUUUUUAGAUUUUGAAAUUUAGGGAUAAUAGCUCUUAGGUUUGGGUACCACUUUGCUGCAGUUUAAGAAAGGGGGAAGGGAACUCAUUUAUUAAACAUCAAUCACGUGCUGUGUUCUGUUUGUUUUCUAGUCAUCAUAUCACACACCUUUACGACAGCUCACUGAAGGAAGGUGAUACUGUUCCCAUUUUGUAGAUGGAAUAGACAAAACCUGAAUUUAAGUAGCUUGCUCAAGGUUCCAUAUUGAAUAUGGAAAGUUCAAAUCAUCUCAGUAAUGAAUAUACCAUAUAUACUUGCUGUAUUGUAUCUAUGAUAAUUCAGUUACCCACAAUACCCUUUUAAAUUUCUGUUAAUGACAUACCUUUAAAUGUCUCCUUGAUGAACAGAAUCAUGGUCUUUAAAAACAUUUUCAUGGGUUGAUUGCAUUUUCAAGCUCUAAAGGAUUGAAAGAUAAAUCUUCACGUUAAAGGUAAGAGUGAAGUAUCUGCUCUUGGGUUACAGAACCAGAUAGUACUAGAACUAAGAUUACAGGGUAAAGCUGCUUUUAUCUUUUUUCUUUUUCUUUUUCUUUUUUUUUUUGACAUGGGGUCUCACUGUAUUGCCCAGGCUGGAAUGCAGUGGCAUGAUCUCAGCUCACGGCAGCCUCUGCCUCUUGGGCUCAAGCGAUUCUCCUGCUUCAGCUUUCCAAGUAUUUGGGACCACAGGCGCACACCACAGGCCUGGCUAAUGUUUUUGUUUUGUUUUUGGUAGAGACGGGGUUUCACCAUGUUGCCAGGCUGGUCUCGAACUCCUGAGCUCAAGUGAUUCACCCACCUUGGCCUCACAAAGUGUCAGGCUUACAGGCGUGAGCCACUGCGCCCGGCUCACAGGGUAAGGCUUCUGUCUGGUGUGUUGUAUUACGGAUUUUGCUUAAUAGGCACAGUGAGGCAUUAAAAAGAAAAUUCAGUAUGCCUGUAGAAAGGAUAAUCCUUGUUUAAAGUCUCCAAAUUGCAGUCAAAGAUGUUUUGACUGUGCCUUUUUUUGUUCCCCUGCUGUCCCUUAUGUAGACUUCUGUCAGUACCCAUGGCAGCCUGUCAUCUUGUUGACAUCUCCUUCUGGACUGUGAGCUCUGUAUCUGGCUUGUUUUUCAUCCCCAGCUUCUAGUUCACAAUUAGGUAGAACCCUAUUACUCUUUGAAGAAGGAACAAGAAAAUGUGGGCCAGUUUUCAUUUGCCAUUCUUCCAUGUGAGUUAGUAUGGUUCGUAAGUAUUCCUGGUGAUACGCUAGUAUUGGCAAUUCUGUGAGGUUGAACAAAGGGGUGGUAUGGUGUGCUAGCGUGGGAAUUAGGAGACCUCUGGGUCUUGACAGUGCCCUGGCCACUAAGCAAAGGCAGUUCAUCCUUGGAGUCUCAAUGUGCUUUUUUGUUAAUUGAGAUAUGCUUGAAGUAUCAGCCCUAAAUAGUCUGAUUCUGUGACCUACAAACCCUUACUUAAUUCAGUGUUACUAUAAAUGAUUCUUCCCUUAAACCUACUUUUUACUUAGCAAAAGAGAAAAAAAAAAAAAGGAAACGCUCAUGUCAGGCUGCCUGGGUUUGAACCCCAGAUCCCCUCUUAGUUGGAGGCAAGUUGUAUGAUGCUUCAGCUUUUGGUUCCUGCCUCCUAAGGUUGUUAGGAGUUACUGUGUGUAGCUGCUUAGAACAUUGCCUGGGUCUCAGUAAGCCGCUUAAGUGACUGCUCUCAUUUUCGCUGUAAAGCACCAUACUGUAAUAACAUCCCAUGAAGCAUGGGGCGGGGAAGAGUAUAUGGUACCUUAUGGACUUUGAUGUGGUGGGGUAGUAGGUAAAUUCUGAAUAUGUAAGCUACAUAGUAUUCUUUUUGUAACUAAAGGAUAAAAGUUUUAAGAUGGGCAUGUAAUAUGGCUAGCACUGGAUUUUAAUGAUGAGCCAGAGUAAUAAGGCUGGCAAGGGGAGUUUUUGUUUUGUAAUAAAUCUCUUACACCUGCACAUCCAGUUCUUUUUAAAAACACGUUUGAAGAGGCUCCAUAUUUCUCAGUGAAGCUGUUGGGGUUCAUGUUAUUUUUGAAAAUCAUCUUGCAAUUUAUUUCAGCAUCAGACUGAACCACCCAAAGAAAAUUAGUCUAUUUCUGAACAGUUUUUUCAGAAACCAUAUUGGUCUGAUCACCCAACAUUUAUAGAAAUAGGCGCUUAAGGCCUAGAGGCAUUUCAGAAAGGAGAAUGAGAAAUACUGUGGUCAAGAGUAGUGUUCAGAUGGAGAACAUCAAGCAUCUGCUCUGCCCUUCCACACACAUCCUCAUUUCAUCUUCACAACUGCCCUAGGUAACCUUGUUAUCUGUAAUGAAACAGCCUCAAGGAGCACAGAGGCACUCACUCCUCACGUUUGGUCUGUUGCCAUUUCCGGCUUGGUUGGAAUAGGGUAGGAGCCUUUUGGCAGGGAGCACAUUCUCAGUAAUGCAGAGUGCACUCACCUGGGUUCUAGCUUCAACACUUAGGAUUUGCUUGAUAUUUUGUAUUCUCUGAGGCACUGCCUGUAUUUGUUUCUGCUAUCACAGUCCAGAGUCAAGCUUCAUUUAUAAAGACUGGGCAGGGCAUGGUGGCUCACUCCUGUAAUUCCAGCACUUUGGGAGGCUGAGGUGGGUGGAUCACUUUAGGUCAGGAGUUCAAGACCAGCCUGGCCAACAUGGUGAAACCCCAUCUCUACUAAAAAAUACAAAAAGGCCGGGCACGGUGGCUCACACCUGUAAUCCCAACACUUUGGGAGGCCAAGGUGGGCAGAACACCUGAGGUCAGGAGUUCAAGACCAUCCUGGCGAACAUAGUGAAACCUCGCCUCUACUAAAAAUACAAAAAUUAGCCAGGUGUGGUGGUGCAUGCCUGUAAUCCCAGCUACUUGGGAGGCUGAGGCAGGAGAAUUGCUUAAACCUGGGAGGUGGAGAUUGUGGUGAGCUGAGAUCGUGCCACUGCACUCCAGCCUGGGAGAUAGAACGAGACUCCAUCUCAAAAAAGAACAAAAACAAUUAGCCGAGCGAGGUGGUGCACGCCUGUAAUCCCAGCUACUCAUGAGGCUGAGGCAGGAGAAUCACUUGAACCCAGGAGGAGGAGGUUGUAGUGAGUCAAGGUUGCACCACUGCACUCCAGCCUGGGUGACAGAGUGAGACUGUCUCAAAAAAUAAGUACAUAAAUAAUAAGUAAAAGCUACUAACAAUUAAAAAAUAAAUAAAUAAAGACAAGACUGUCUGGAAAAUGGCUCUCCUAAAAGGACCAGUUGCCAUCAUCCACAGUGGAAGAUUCAAAGCAGUUGGUCCUUGGUACGUAUGAGAAGCGGAUUUCAUUCCCUUGAAUUCUACAGAGCAGUUUAUUAGAGUGAAUGCAUUUUAAGGCCUUGCAUUUGAUAUGUCAUCCAGUUCAUAAUCAAGUUGCCUUUUUCUGGCUAAAACAUAAUGAUUAUGUAUUUUUCUCAUUUGGUCCUACAAGCUGCUGGCCCUUUGUCCCUCCACUGUGGGAAUCAGAUCUAGAGGAGGCUGAGCCUGCAGACACAGCAGUGGCCAAAAGGUCACUCUAAGUGUUUUGUCUUGACUCCUUACUUGAAGUCCACCCAGCUAGCACACAUCUGGUUUAUACUGAAGCCCCCUGCCUAGAAAUACUCAUUUCAGGAACCACCAGUAAGCAUCUGUGACCACACAGGCUUUUUGACUGAUGGCUUCCCGGAUCUGGUUUCAAGGGAUAACCCCGUCUGUGUGCAUCUAUGGUCUUCUCUCUACAGCGAGGACUUUGCAGUGCUGCUUGUGGUCCACACAAGGGGCUCAGAGCUGAGUCUGAACUGCUUCAUGGUCACCAGCUCCUGUCCCUUCCAGUCUUGAGAGGCUUUUUUCUCCAGAUGGAACCUUUCCUUCCCGCCGUUUUCUCGGUCUCUGGCUGUUUUUCUCUUGUGCCCGUCUAAUUGGACACCUCCUGGCUUCCAUCUCUGUGGUUCUCCUGCCUCACUUCCUGUUCUGUUGUUUUUCCGUUUUGUCAAAAUAUCUCCUAUGUUCUUGGCUUCCUUUUCGUCGCCAGGUUUUCAGCUUUCCUUUAGCUCUUCUUCUAAUAUGGCUUCUGCCCACAAAAGCCUGCUCUGUCAGGAUCUCAUGGUUCUCCACUUGCCAGAACCUUCUUCAGCCUCAGUUCCUCGGCCUCAACUUGUACGUUUAACCCAUUGACCACCACCCCCCAAAUUCACCUUCAUUUCUUUGACCCUGCUCCUCACUCCUUUUCUGUUGAGGAAUCUGUUGACUAACUCCAGGCUCACUCAGGCUCACCGUCCUGCUCUCUGCACCAGCCUUUCCAGAGCGUGCCAGUUCUCAUGGCUUCAUCUGUUAACUGUUGAUCACUUCAGUCCUGAUUUUUAGACCUAAAUGGUUUCCUUAACGCCAUUCUAACUGCCUGUGACUCAUUUUCACUUACAGUGUUUAUUGUAACGCCAAACCAACAAAUCACAGGUGCUUGCUUCUCUCCAUAAAUCUCCCCAGUCUAACUUUUUGUCAUUCAACAUGACUCGUUUAUCCAACCUGAAAUCGCAUAUAGCCCCAAGUAUGGUGUUUUGUACACAGGUAUUUAAUAAGUGACUUCCAGUUUUGGCUCUGCUAUGAAUAAAAAGAGAUUUCAGUUCUCUUCACUUUGAAAUCUAACAACUCAGAGAACAUUGAAGAAAUUGGAAUUUAGUUGGGAUGAAAUACUUGUGGUUUAAAAUAUUUCUGUUCAUAUUUUCUAAUUUGUUGCCGGAGGUCUUGGGUUUUCUAUUUGAGUGCUUGCAAACUCAAUGUGAUUUCUGUCAGCAUAUCUUAGGUUUGUUUGUUAUGAAACUUAUGCAGUGUGAGGUUCUAUCUGAAAAUGUUAUUUAGCUAUCUUCUGGGACUAUUUAAUGAAAGUGGGGUCAUGAAUCCUUAAAAUUCUUGUGCAGCUUUGAGAAACAUUUCUGUUAUUUGGGUAUCAGUUUGUAAGUGUGGUAAAGCCAAGAUGGAAACGAGCACUUUGCUUUCUUGGUUGUUGUUACUGGUCUAACCUCCUGCUUGAACUAGUCUGCUGUCCUGUCAAAUGCAUCUUUUUAUUUACAUGUCCCUUAAAUUAAAGCUGAUCAUGAAAGUA